GUUUCCGGCGCGGCCCAGCGAGCUCGGCAACCUCGGCGCAGCGAGCGCGGGCGGCCAGCCAGGGCCAGGGGGCGGUGGCGGCCAAGGUCCGACCGGGUGCCAGCUGUUCCCAGCCCCCGCCUCGGGCCCGCCGCCGGCGCCGCCAUGGGCAAGAAGCACAAGAAGCACAAGGCCGAGUGGCGCUCGUCCUACGAGGAUUAUGCCGACAAGCCCCUGGAGAAGCCUCUAAAGCUAGUCCUGAAGGUCGGAGGAAGUGAAGUGACUGAACUCUCAGGAUCCGGCCACGACUCCAGUUACUAUGAUGACAGGUCAGACCAUGAGCGAGAGAGGCACAAAGAAAAGAAAAAGAAGAAGAAGAAGAAGUCCGAGAAGGAGAAGCAUCUGGACGAUGAGGAAAGAAGGAAGCGAAAGGAAGAGAAGAAGCGGAAGCGAGAGAGGGAGCACUGUGACACGGAGGGAGAGGCUGACGACUUUGAUCCUGGGAAGAAGGUGGAGGUGGAGCCGCCCCCAGAUCGGCCAGUCCGAGCGUGCCGGACACAGCCAGCCGAAAAUGAGAGCACACCUAUUCAGCAACUCCUGGAACACUUCCUCCGCCAGCUUCAGAGAAAAGAUCCCCAUGGAUUUUUUGCUUUUCCUGUCACGGAUGCAAUUGCUCCUGGAUAUUCAAUGAUAAUAAAACAUCCCAUGGAUUUUGGCACCAUGAAAGACAAAAUUGUAGCUAAUGAAUACAAGUCAGUUACGGAAUUUAAGGCAGAUUUCAAGCUGAUGUGUGAUAAUGCAAUGACAUACAAUAGGCCAGAUACCGUGUACUACAAGUUGGCGAAGAAGAUCCUUCACGCAGGCUUUAAGAUGAUGAGCAAAGAGCGGCUGUUAGCUUUGAAGCGCAGCAUGUCGUUUAUGCAGGACAUGGAUUUUUCUCAGCAGGCAGCUCUUUUGGGCAAUGAAGAUACAGCUGUUGAGGAACCUGUCCCUGAAGUUGUACCAGUACAAGUAGAAACUGCCAAGAAAUCCAAAAAGCCGAGUAGAGAAGUUAUCAGCUGCAUGUUUGAGCCUGAAGGGAAUGCCUGCAGCUUGACGGACAGUACCGCAGAGGAGCACGUGCUGGCGCUGGUGGAGCACGCAGCUGACGAAGCUCGGGACAGGAUCAACCGGUUCCUCCCAGGCGGCAAGAUGGGCUAUCUGAAGAGGAACGGGGACGGGAGCCUGCUCUACAGCGUGGUCAACACGGCCGAGCCGGACGCUGAUGAGGAGGAGACCCACCCGGUGGACUUGAGCUCGCUCUCCAGUAAGCUACUCCCAGGCUUCACCACGCUGGGCUUCAAAGACGAGAGAAGAAACAAAGUCACCUUUCUCUCCAGUGCCACUACUGCGCUUUCGAUGCAGAAUAAUUCAGUAUUUGGCGACUUGAAGUCGGACGAGAUGGAGCUGCUCUACUCAGCCUACGGAGAUGAGACAGGCGUGCAGUGUGCGCUGAGCCUGCAGGAGUUUGUGAAGGAUGCUGGGAGCUACAGCAAGAAAGUGGUGGACGACCUCCUGGACCAGAUCACAGGCGGAGACCACUCUAGGACGCUCUUCCAGCUGAAGCAGGUGUCCCCCGGAGACCGUGACUGUGUGCUCACCACUCCCAGCGCACUCGUAACUCUCUAUUUCCAUCUUCAUCUUUCAUCUCUGUCACUUUCCUUCAUCCUGAAGAGUUUAAAAAAAUAUUUCCUGUAGUUCAGAUUUACUGACAGUGAUCUCUCAGCAUUGGCUUCUCUGAAAGUCUUUAUUUCAUCUUCAUUUUUGAAAUUCAUUUUCCCUGUGUAUGGAAUUUUAGAUGACCUUUUUUCCCAUCUACUGUAAAAUAGGUUUGACUUGCAUUGUUGCUAUAAAAAAGCAUCUGGGCCAAGCAUGGUGGCUCACACUUGUAAUCCCAGCACUUUGGGAGGCCGAGGCGGGCAGAUCCAAGGUCAGGAGGUCGAGACCAUCCUGGCUAACACGGUGAAACCCCGUCUCUACUAAAAAAUAGAAAAAAUUAGCUGGGCGUGGUGGCAGGUGCUUGUAGUCCCAGCUACUCGGGAGGCUGAGGCAGGAGAAUGGCAUGAACCCGGGAGGCAGAGCUUGCAGUGAGCCGAGAUCAUGCCACUGCACUCCAGCUUGGGCCACAGAGCCAGACCCCAUCUCCAAAAAAAAAAAAAAAGCGUCUGAAGUCAUUGUCAUCUUUGUUUCCCACAUGUGACGUGUCUUUUCGGCCAGAUCUGACCUGAAGUCUGCUUUUGUACAGACCACAAGCCAGGAAUGUCUUUUACAUCUUUAAAAGGGUGUUUACAGAAAAGAAAAGGAAGAAGAAGAUGCUUCGGGCAGCGUGUGGCUCACAGAGCCUCGGCUGCUCACUCCCGGGCCCUCGGCAGGACGGGAUCUGGCCGGUGCUCUAGGAGCUUUUGAACUUUUAUCUUUCUUUAUCAGUGAUUUUCAGCAUUGUAUUUUCCAGGUGCCUUGGUGGGCUUUUCUUUGUGUUCUACUUAGCAUUUGUUGUUUCUUGGAUCUGUCUGUAGUUUUCAUCAUAUUUGGAAGAUUUUUAGCCAUUACUCAAAUGUCAUUUUCCACCACUGCCUCUUCCUCCUCCUGCUGGACUGUGGCACUCUGAGGACAGCUCGUGUUAUCUCACAUGGCACCGACACUGUGCUGCCGCACCAGGCUGCUGCAGAUUAGUUUCUGAUGCUGUUGGCUAAGUUCACUCACCUGUUCUCUGGCCACACCUGAACCUGUUAUCCCAGAUCAGUUUUCACUGAUGAUGUCGUCCCGCGCUGCUCAUCACUUGGGCUCCAUUUGCUGCUUUUGUGUAUCUUCUCUCAUGUUGUGUGUAUGUUUUUCCUUACAUCCUUGAGCCACGUUCGUAUUUAUUGCUGCUGCUUUUGAAGUCCUCAGUCACUGAGUCUGUCGCCUCUGCCGUUUCCGGUUCUGUUUCUGUUUGACACUUUGCUGCACUUGGAGCUGUGGGCCAUUGUGCACGUGCCUGGUGGACAGUCCUGACCCUCGCUGUCUGAUAAAAAAGCACUGGCCACAUGGCCGCUGGGAAAUUUGAAUGUGGCCAGUCUGAAUUUAGAUGUGAUGUGUGAGCUACAAACUAGAUCUUAAAAAACUAAUGCAAAAAACGUAAAAAUAUGAGUAACGAUUUCUUAUGGCCCACAUGUUGGAAUAAAAACAUCUUCAAUAAAUUUGUCUAAGUAAAAUGCAUUAGUUAAUUGAAUGUUAAGAGUAAUUUUAAUGUGGCAGCUAGAAUUUUAAGAGCUGGGUAUGGUGGCAUGCACCUGUCAUCAGCUCCACAGGAGGCUAAGGUGGGAGGAUCACUUGAGGCCGGGAGGUCGAGGCUGCAGUGCGAUUGCACCACCGCACUCUAGGCAAUAGAGCAAGACCCUGUCUCAAAAAAAAGAUAAAAAAACAUUUAGAACGAGGCGUGUGCUCGCGUUAUGUCUGCUGGGCAAGGCUGAUCUGGGUUCUUUCUCUCUUUCAGAGAAUACUGAUGAUCAUUUUGGCAGUUGUUACUUGUGGAUAAUGGCCGGAUCCUACCAGGCUUGUCUGGGGUGGGUCCAGGGCAGCCUUAUUCUAGGGUUCGUGUAGCCUUAAUGCUAAGGAGUGGCCCUUCGGGGAGCCCUGUCUUUUCAGCGUGGUCUCUGCUGUGGGUGGAGUUCGGAUGAGUCUCUGUCCUUCCCAGGCUCUGAGAACGUUUGGCUCAUGGCUCCCAAGGAGGGGUCAGUCCCUUGACCUGACGGUUUCAUCUGUGCUUGUUACAGAUGAACUGGGGUCCACAUGCCUGGUGCAGUAAACCCAGACACCCAUGCCGAGGUUUUGUCAUAGAAAGGACGUGUGUAUUUGCAGGGCGCCAAGCAAGGUGGGCCAGGAGGCUCAUGUAUAAAUCCUGGCCUCCCCCACUGGCUACAGGCAAGGCUUGUAAAGCGGGGGUAGAUCUCAGGAAAGCAGAACUGAAAGGCAGAGUCGUGCAUAAGGACACAGAGGUUACAUGUCGGCUUGGCCUAGAAGGGCGGUAUCUGCAAGCAGGGCCUUAUAGGUUAUAGGUGGAUUCAAAGGUUUUCUGAUUUGCAGCUGGUUAAGGAGGAGAAGCUUUGUUUAAAAAUUUGGGGUGAAGAGAAAAGAAUGUUAGCUUAGGCUUGUGGGUGUGGCUUCCUCCAGGCCCGUCAGGAAGAAAUUCAGAACAAAGAACGGGGUCAGAGCUCAGUCUUCAGUUUCUCCUUAUCUGAGCCCUUCAUGCCAGUAGAUUAGUUUGUUGGGGAGGUCCUAGGUGGAGGGUCCAGGUUUCUGAAAGACAACUCAGGGAUAUACAUUAAGAUGUUAUCUUUACUUUCUUUCUUUUUUUUUCUUUUUGAGACAUAGAGUCUCACUCUGUCACCCAGGCUGGAGUGCAGUGGCGUGAUUGUGGCUCACUGCAACCUCUGCCUCCCUGAUUCUAGCGAUUCUCCUGCCUCAGCCUCCCGAGUAGCUGGGAUUACAGGCAUGCGCCACCACACCUGGCUAAUUUUUGUAUUUUUAGUAGAGGCGGAGUUUCGCCAUGUUGGCCAGGCUGGUCUUUAACUCCUGACCUCAAAUGAUGCAUCCAUCUCAGCCUCCCAGAGUGGUAGGAUGUUGUCUUUUCUUUCUACAGGGAACAGUGCUGGGAGGUUGUCUUUACUUUCUACAGGGAACAAACAUCUGUCUCCACCUUCCUUGACUGUUGUUUUAGGAUACUGUUACCUUCUUGCUUAUCAAGUCGCUGAUUUACUUCUCAGAGUUAUCUAAGUAACUGGAAUUUCCCUUGAAGGAACUCAAGAUUUUCCUUGAUUUCCAUGCUUGGAGGGCUCGCAGGCCCCUGAAGAGAGGGUUGCAGCCAGGCGGGAGUCCCCAAGCAGAUUUCUGCAGCUCUGAGGAGCAGCCCCCUCUGCAGAGCCUGCCCCACCAGCUCGUGGUUCUGACUCUGAGCUCUGGUCACCCUCCCGUGUCGUGGCCUGCAGGCUCCUUCCAGGCAGGAAGCUGGCCCCCCCAACACAGCGUUAGAAUCAGGCAUUGCUGUGGGGUAGGGAAAGUGACCCCCUCACAGCCCGGAAAUGGGAAGGCUCUGUGGUUUCCUCUCUGGGUUCCAGUUAGAUUCCUUUCGGGAAAGUGAACUUGGAUAUGGAGUUGAGUGACCCCGAGUGCACCCCCGCAGUAAAUGAUGCUCAGGACUAAAGUGACUGAAGGCUUUUGGGGAAACAGAUGCGAACAAAACAGCAGUAUUCAUUUUCUAAUUAAAAGCUUGUGAAAAUCGA